UUUCUUUUUUUUUUUUUUUUUUUGAGACAGAGUCUCACUCUUGUCGCCCAGGCUGGAGUGCAAUGGCGCGAUCUCGGCUCCCUGCAACCUCCAUCUCCCGGGUUCAAGCGAUUCUCCUGCCUCAGCCUCCCGAGUAGCUAGGAUUAUAGGCACCCGCUACCACGCCCAGCUAAUUUUUGUAUCUUUAGUAGAGAUGAGGUUUCACCCUGUUGGCCAGGCUGGUCUCAAACUCCUGACCUCAGGCGAUCCUCCCGCCCCCGCUUCCCAAAGUGCUGGGAUUACAGGCGUGAGCCACCGCACCCGACCAGUCCUGUGCUUUCUGAUACAAUAUCAUCCCCCUUCUUUGCCUCACCAUCUCCCAUGGGCAUGAUCAGUUAACAAUUGCUGGAAAAAUCAACUUUACCUGAACAUUUAGGAAGCUAUUUGGGAUGUCCAGUGUUUUUCUUCCUCUUGAAAAACACUAACGCAGGUCUGCAUUUAUUAGGGGAGUGGGGAUCAUCAUCUGUCUCUUCUGCCGCUUUGCUCUAAAGGAACUCAAGAGCCCAUAAGCAUUUUCCCUGAAAAGGUCAUCAUUUCCAAAGAAAUGAGAGCUCAUUUAAAGUUUCUAGGUAUGAAAAUCCUAGGUUCUUGCCCUUCUCCUUCCACUUCUUGGUGGCAGUGGGUAGGGAAUCAAACAUCAGAUGACCUUCUUCCUCUCUGGUUUCUCCCCACCGCUGUAUCAGACCAGGAAGGUGAAAGAGGGUCAUGCUGACUCUCCUAACUCCCAUCCCUCUGCCACGCCUCCCCUCCACUGCAGCACUGGCAUGGUUACCUGUGAAGCAACUGCCAAAGACAACAUGGGCAGCCUUUGUGUCUGGGUAGCCCAGUUCACAAUGGCGGUUAAUGGAAGUUCCUGUUCAGACGCCCUCCAACUCCCCAGAGGGCGUGGGCAUCUCCUCUUAUGUAAAGGGGAAAUCUUAGGAAAUUUUUAAUUUUUCCUUUAAUCAGUCAGCAAGGUCAUAAGAGGCUUUGUAAGUAUUCAUUAGAAGUGGAAAGCAGGCCGGGCGUGGUGGCUCACACCUGCAAUGACAGCAUUUUGGGAGGCCAAGGCAGGCGGAUCACCUGAGGUCAGGAGUUUGAGACCAGCCUGGCAAACAUGGUGAAACCCCAUCUCUACUAAAAAUACAAAAAUUAGCCAGGUGUGGUGGUGCGCCUGUAGUCCCAGCUACUCAGGGAGGCUGAGACAGGAGAAUUGCUUGAACCUGGGAGGCAGAGGUUGCAGUGAGCCGAGAUGGCGCCACUGCACUCCAGCCUGGGUGACAGAGCAAGAGUCCGUCUCAAAAAAAAAAAAAAAGAAGAAGUGGAAAGCAAAAUUUCUAGUGAACAUACCAUAGAAAUUUAUAGCAGAUCUACUGUGUGUCAAGUUUUGUUCUGAACAGGUGGAGAGGAGGGCACAGAAAUGAACAGGCAAUGAACAAGGAGCCUGGAACUCUUGGUGAAUCGAGGUGUGCAUGAGAGACAGGCAAAUGAAUAAGCAUACUGUAAAUCAAGGCCAGAGAGUGCCUCUGAAUGGGGACCUGACAGGGUGGAAACCGAUCUUCUUGUCUUGAAGUCUUCCUUGAGGGAAAGGAUGAGUUUCACUGGAGUGAGGAAGAGGUAAGGAGGGCUUUUCUCCGUGGGGGUAGCAUCUGCCUUCUGGGGUCGGUCUAAGGGAGGUGUGGGGAAGGGGCUGGCCUCACGGGCCUGCACCCUAUGCUACCACACCGGCUUGCUCUCAGAAGGGCCCCACACUUGGUUUAAUGCUCUGCUGUUGCUGCCUUGAAAUUCUUACUAAGUUUUGAACUAAUUAUUAUUUAGUUAAUAAAUAACAAAUUAUUUUCAUUUUGUACCAGGCCCUGCAAAUCAUGCAGCUGGUCCUGCCUAUGGAGAUGGGACUGUAAAAGUAGAUUUGGCUGGAUUGUGAAGAGCUUUGCCCGUCAAGCUUGGGAACAUCUGACUUUAUUCCAUAAGCAGUAGGGAGCCAUGGAAAGUAUGCUGACAGGGUUGGGAGAAAGGGGCACUGGAGGCUGUGAGACCAGGGAGGCCAGCAGUCCACCGAGGGAGGCUGAUAACACCACGCUGGGAUAGACACCGAGAGCUGCAGUUCCCACACCUGGUGGAGAUAGGCCGGCUCUGGGCACUGGGAAGGAGGCCGAGAGCGGCCGUUGCAGGUGGCUGAGGCUUCUAGCUGAGCAGAUCCUGCACAUCAAGAAUGCAGGAGAAAGAAGUCCCUCAGCCAGUGGCAGCGAGGCAGAUGUUUUGCAGGAGUGGGGCAAGGCUCUUUCCAGAAAGACCCGGAAAUCUCUGGUGGGACAGCUUGUAGAAACAUGCACUGCAGCUGCUCAGCUACAGCAAAUGACCUGCAGAUCAAGGUUUUUGUCAGUAUCGAGAGCUUCACUAGAACAAAUAUUCAUCCAAAAAUAAACUUCCCGUUCUUCCUGUUUUUAUAACUUGCCUAUUUCCUCUGAGUUUGAGGCUGGGCUCCAGUUCCAUGGGUUAUUAAUCUUCAGAGGAUCAAGACCUCUAUAGAAGUAUUUCCUGUACAUGUUUAUCUACCCAGCCCUAAAUUAUAUUCUCCAAAUGAUAAGAGAACUUUUCCAUACUCGUGUGUCAGACUUCUCCUUAGGGAGAUUUCGAUUAGGCACCACAGCAAGUAGGGCCAAACCAGAAAGCCUUAUCUCAGAACAUAGGGAACCCACGUAACGGUGGGGAGCGGCCUUUGGUGGGUUUUGAUGGGCACUCAGCCUCCCUCCUCCAUGUGAAAGGUAGCUUCUUUCUGGCCAGAGUUCUAAGGACAUAAAGUAAUAGCUGAAGAGGGCCCUAUCUGAGGAUAUUUUAAAUUCCCUGUUGAAUACCACAGGGGAUAUUAGCUAAAGAAAUUCUGCUCCUUUGAAGAGCUCAAAAUACCCCUCAUUGGACCAUCACUUGUUCUUACAGCAUCUUCCAACUAGAAACAGGGCCCCGGCCUCACAGACAAGGGAACUAGAGUGAACUUGGUGCUCAUGACAGCACAGAGCAAGAGGGAAAAGCUCUGUUGAAGCUUGGGCCGAGUUCAGACCUGAUAGACAAGUAUGGUUAAGCAGGCGUGGGCGCUUUACUCAUCGGCCCGGUCCACCUGCCUCUGGAGCCCUUCCUUGCUCUCCUACUUUUUGUGCUUACAGACGCCAAGCUAGCAUGCCGGUGGUAUUUUUAAAACGUAAGCCUUCUUGUAUGACUCUUGCAGAGAGGCGGUGGUGACCGGGCUGCGUGGGUGGCGGCUUGUGCCGCAGCGGAACUUGGAGAAAGGCCAGCUGCCUUUUACUGAGGCCUUCCGAGGUGGGGCUGGGAUGCCACAUUUUUCAAACACACCACCGCAAGGCAGCACCCCUCCCCCUUAGAGAUCCAGGUGACUCCACUGAGAAUUACUGCGCCACACCGUGGCUUCUAGACCCACACUGUCAAGUAUGUAGUCCUUGCCACCUGGGCUGUUGAACCUGGAAAUGAGGCUUGUACGAACUGACUAAAAGUGCAAAAUACACAUUGGAUUUUGAAGCCUUAUUACAAAAAGAAAAAAAAGAAUGUGAAGUAUCUCAUUAAUGAUUAUUUUAUUUUGGUUACUGUGGAAACAAAUAUUUUAGAUAUCUUGGUUUGUGUCAACUAUGUUAUAAUUAAUGACACCUGCUUUUUAAUUACUCUUUAAAUGUGACUACUAGAAAAUUUUAAACUGUGUAUGUGGCUCAGUUUCCAUUUCUAUGGGACAGUACCGCUAGUCUGUGCUGUGAGUUCAGCUGCCAGUUGUGGCUUUGAAACCAGUACAUUCCCAGAGGCUCCUCUCCUUAGUGGUCUGGCUGAGGGGGGGUUACCCAGCCCUAACCCUAGACUGCCUAGGGUAGUGUGUGGGACAGCCUGCUUCCAGGCAAAAAGUUAAUAAUUUAAUAAGCAGCAGCAAGAAUUUCUAAAAAUCCUUUCCAAAGCACCCCCCCUGGCUUUUUUUUCUUCUUCUUCUUCGUAGCCUUCUUCCUGGACCAGCCUUCUUCCUGGAAAUCUUUUUUUAAAUGCAGAACUCUUCCCUUCUGUCCCACAUGGGACCUGUGGAGGUGAUGGUGUCCAGAGGGGCUAUUGUUUUAUUUUAUUUUCUUGUUUAAAUUGUUCUUUUGCCCACAGGUCAGGCUGCUCCAGUAGCUGCCUUUUAACCCUUCCUCUGCAGGACCAUCUCAGAAACCACCCAGCAAAGACUGGGAAGCCACUCUUUUAGACCAGUUCCCCCUCCCUUCUCCCUUUGGAGUGGUUACUCAAGCGCAGACAUAUAUUGGGAAAACACAAGGUGGAUGUGAAACCAAGGAAACUCCUGCUUUGAGAAGUACAGAAGUGCAGACCCACAACCAACCUCCUAAUGUCAAGCUGGCAUUUUAGGAAAAAGGUGUGUGUGGUGGGGGGAAUUCCACUGGUGUCUGAAAGCCCCCAAGUAAUUCCCUGUUGCAAGGAGGAGUCUCAUGUUGACUUCAGAGGUCCAGGCAGAACCUGUUGAAUUGCACAGUUCCCAUUUGCUAGAGGAUAUUACACGGUGAGAUCUCUCUGCUCAGGGACCGGGGCUGAGGGCUUCUGUCAUCAGCCAGUGGAGCGGCCCUGCACCGAGGCACCUCCCUGCUUUUGCCACAUUUUGCCCACCCUGCUGUCUGUCAUGUACUGAACCUUUGCUGGAAUAAUUGCCAUAGGUGUCAACAUGUAUUAAGGGCUUGCUGUAUGAAGGUACUAUGCAAAGUGCCUUUUGCUAUGUGCAGCUAACUAGCAUAACAAACCCCAAGAUGCCCCAGAGGAGAUACUCUUGUUUCCCUGUUUUGCAGAUAGAGAAACUGCAGGUUAGAGAGAUGAAAUAAGUUGACCAAGCUAGAAAUUGGUGGGCAGGGAACACAACUUGGGCCAUGCUGCUUUAGAGCUGCCGAGUGUUUAACUGUUAAGGUGUCAUUCUGCACUGCCUAGACCAGCCCAUGUAUGUUACCGUUCCAUUCUGCAUGAGCAUUUGUCUAUUAUCAAGACAUCUGCUGGUGCAGGCUGGGACACAACACCAAGGGAGGGUUAAAUUCUGGGUUGCCAAACCAGCUGAGCUACGAGUUGAGGAGCACUGAGCGCCUCUGAGCUUUGCUGGGCUAACUUGGUGAGGUUUGGAAAUGAGCAAAGGGGUAAGAAAGAGCCAUGUGUCUGGAGUCAGGCUGCCUAUUUGGUUUGACCUCUCAAUGGCUUCAUAGGUUGGGCUACUCCUUCUCUGGGCAGCAGUUUCCCCAGUUCUAAAAUGGGGAUCCUAAGAGCGCCUUCCUCAGAGAACUGCAAUGAGAAUUAAAGAGGACACAUAAAGGCAAAGUGUACUUGGCAUGUCAAUGUCAUUAAUAUCAUUAAUGCCAUUUAAUGCUCUUUGAUGGAGCAUAAUCUAUAUAACAUGUAAUAGAAGAUAUAAUCGUGGCUUGAAUUUUUUGUUGUUUUAAGGCAAACACUUCAGAGCAUGUACCUUUGCAUCUGAACACAUACGUCUGUAUUUGAAUGUUAUAUCUUUCAAAGCCAUGACCUCACCUCAGGAGACUCCUCUCUCAACUUGAUCUCACAGCCAUUUACUGGAAACAUUUUCAGAAGCCUUUGUGGAACUCUUUUCAGAAGAAAAAAAGAGAGAAAGUGGGGGCCAUACUUGGCACUAUGACAGCUAUAUUGUGCGUGUCAAGGCUGUGGUUAUGACCAGAGAUGACUCCAGCGGGGGAUGGUUCCCACAGGAAGGAGGCGGGAUCAGUCGCGUCGGGGUCUGUAAGGUCAUGCACCCCGAAGGCAAUGGACGAAGCGGCUUUCUCAUCCAUGGUGAACGACAGAAAGACAAACUGGUGGUAUUGGAAUGCUAUGUAAGAAAGGACUUGGUCUACACCAAAGCCAAUCCAACGUUUCAUCACUGGAAGGUCGAUAAUAGGAAGUUUGGACUUACUUUCCAAAGCCCUGCUGAUGCCCGAGCCUUUGACAGGGGAGUAAGGAAAGCAAUCGAAGACCUUAUAGAAGGUUCAACAACGUCAUCUUCCACCAUCCAUAAUGAAGCUGAGCUUGGCGAUGAUGACGUUUUUACAACAGCUACAGACAGUUCUUCUAAUUCCUCUCAGAAGAGAGAGCAACCUACUCGGACAAUCUCCUCUCCCACAUCCUGUGAGCACCGGAGGAUUUAUACCCUGGGCCACCUCCACGACUCAUACCCCACAGACCACUAUCACCUCGAUCAGCCGAUGCCAAGGCCCUACCGCCAGGUGAGCUUCCCGGACGACGACGAGGAGAUCGUGCGCAUCAACCCCCGGGAGAAGAUCUGGAUGACGGGGUACGAGGAUUACCGGCACGCACCCGUCAGGGGCAAGUACCCGGACCCCUCGGAGGACGCGGACUCCUCCUACGUGCGCUUCGCCAAGGGCGAGGUCCCCAAGCAUGACUACAACUACCCCUACGUGGACUCCUCAGACUUUGGCCUAGGCGAGGACCCCAAAGGCCGCGGGGGCAGCGUGAUCAAGACGCAGCCCUCCCGGGGCAAGUCGCGGCGGCGGAAGGAGGACGGAGAGCGCUCGCGGUGCGUGUACUGCAGGGACAUGUUCAACCACGAGGAGAACCGCCGGGGCCACUGCCAGGACGCGCCCGACUCCGUGAGAACUUGCAUCCGCCGGGUGAGCUGCAUGUGGUGCGCGGACAGCAUGCUCUAUCACUGUAUGUCGGACCCCGAGGGAGACUAUACAGACCCUUGCUCGUGCGAUACUAGCGACGAGAAGUUUUGCCUCCGGUGGAUGGCUCUUAUUGCCUUGUCUUUCCUGGCCCCCUGUAUGUGCUGUUACCUGCCCCUUCGGGCCUGCUACCACUGCGGAGUGAUGUGCAGGUGCUGUGGCGGGAAGCACAAAGCGGCCGCGUGACUCAGUUUCCCUCCCUUCUCCCUCCAUCCGCAGCCACAGGGGAACUCGUCUCUUACAUACUCUCAUCUUCUCCCCCGCUCCCUUCCACUCCAAGGAGCGAGGAGGGCAAGCGGCCUCCCAGCUCCCUGGUACCUCGAGGCACCAUUCCAGCCAGGGACGCUGCCGGGUAGACUCUCCACUCCCCCUGCCGCCCACACUGCAGCAGCCACAUCCAUACACACACGCUCGCACAGUGUUCUGAGGAAGGAACCUUCGCCACAGACUCCUGUACUAUUAACAAUCUGUAACCAAGCUAACUGUCUCAUCCAUGUGUUGAUUUCCUGUUUCCUCCUCCCCCGCCUCUUCCAGUUCAAAGGAGUCUGCAAUUGGAACUGCUGAUUUUCGGUGGGUUUUGUAGUUGAUUUUUCCAAGAGCGUCGAAGACUCUCUUUCUCUUGGUUCACCUUGCCUGUCGCUAGCAAGCAUCUGGUUCAGCGGAAAUGGGAUGUGAGAAUGAUGAAACCCGACAGAAGUAUCUCAGCCUGCAGUCAGUUAUUAUGUAUAGGAGGUGAGCUAGUUAACAAACUUGUACCACAAAACAAUAUCGCUUUAACUUUUCUAAAGCCAAAUUUCCCAUGUAAGCUGCAGUUUCUAUCUUUAGCCCAUCAUCAUUUUCUGCCCCCCCAAAAUCUGUUGAAAUGAUUCACUGAUGCAAAACAUUCACCCGUAAUAGACUGAGAAUUGAGCCUUAACUUCAGAUUAACUUGUGAGAAUCAGGAAAAUUCCUUCAACUGCAUUGCAUCCUCUUGGACCAGGGCUAGAAUGGGGAUUUCAGGUUUCUAUGAGCCUCCCCAUUACCCCUAAAGUAGAACAUUUUUUAAAUUGUGUUGCCACCACUUCUAAAAAUUUAGCAAUAUUAGAAUAGGAUACUAGUGAAGUAAGAAAUUUUGCUUGUUGUUUUGCAAACCAAAUAGUUUCCUCAAACACAAAUCAGUGUUCCCACGAACAAGUUCCAGUUGAGAAACACUAAGGUUAUGGUGAAUAAAACCAUAGGGAGCUUCUUCCCCCCAACCCCUGGCUAUUUUAUAUUAAUGGGGAGAGGGGAUUUUUAAAUGUCAUAAAUUUGAAGAGUGGUGGGUUGCAUUUUCUUCAUGGGUUUAUGUUUUCGUUUCAUUUUGGACUCAAUUUCACAUCACCAAAUUCCUCAUUUAUACUUGGGGAAAAAACAAGGCCAUAUGUAAAAACCCUUCCAAUGCCUAAGUGUCUUUCUCCUGCAACUCCAAACCCAGACUCGCCACUUUGGGUGCACAGGUGGUUAGGUCAGCCAACUGGUUCUGCCUGUCGCCUUGCCACGGAGGAGGCUUCUAAUUAGCUGGAAAAGAGUAUUUUUCUAAUACGUUGCAAGGAUUAGCCAAAUCUUCUUAUUGAAGAAAGAAGAAAAGUGAAGAGUGGUUACCUAUACCUAGCAUAGUACAAUCAGAACCUCGUGGAGACCACCGGGGACAGGCUUGCGGACGCCGGCUGUUCUUCCCGCCACGAUCUUUCUGUGGUAGCGGCCAGCAGAAGACAUGGCCUGCUCCCCACUCCCUUUCCCCACUCCUUCUUUAUUGCACACAGGACACCAGUCUUCAAGGAAAGGGACUUUUUUCCAGUCUGCCAAUCAUAUUGGGAAAGUGCUAGCUGUGCUCACCUUCAUGGGGCUGUUUCCAGCUCGUCCACAAGCUCAUCGAUUUUCUUUAGUAGAUUACCGGUGUAAAUACCCAGUGUGCUUAUGAGUCAGUUAGUAGACGUCUUCAUUCAUUGGAGUAACUGGUUUAGGCUUUCCAGUUUGGAAAAGGAGCAGAGAGCUGUCCAUCUGGAUUGAUGGAAGAAAAGAGAACCUCAUCCAUGCCUGGAGAACAUCUAGAAAACCUUCAGCCAGCCUCCAGUGCUGUCGAGAGACCACCUUCCCCCGACCCGGAGGCACUUCCUUGGGGUCUUUCUCUAGGGUCUCUUCUCUACAAAGCACAACACUAAUGUUCGUUUCCUUAGACCUCAGUUCAAGUGCCCCUAUUUAUUUCAAUAAGAACGCACAUAUCCCAGCUGUUUUUUGUUUGUCACCUCUAUUUAGUUGUUACCUGUUUCUCUCUUCUUUCACCCCUUGUCCUUUUCCACCCUUUUAAGAGUUACGCUAGCAGAUCUUACUCCACGUAUACUUUUUGGUUUGUGAAGGCAUCGGUUAAGGGCACAAAGACAGCCAUGGGGACAUUUAUGUAAAUACGUCUCUAAUUGCCACACUGCAGCUGAACAGUGUGUAGUAUUUUCCCAGUCAGCUUUGCCAUACUGACGUCAAUCAUUUGAGAGAAAUUAUUCAGAUUUUAUUUUUGUAUCUGUGGUAACAAAACAUUAACCAAAAGAUUUUCUGUCCAGAAGCCUCCCCGACCCCCCAAGCUAUUUGCUCACAUUAACAAAUUAAAGUGCCUGAAGCAUAAUUCAUUCUUUACCUGUAUACUAAAAACCCUGUUGUAUUGAUUUUUUUAUAAUAAGCCUUUUUACCUCUGUGUAAAAAAUAUAUAUACAAGUGUAUGAUGUACAUUUUAGUUCUUAACUUUUUUUUAUGGUUUCUAAUAUGUAUGACCAAUGUAGCCAUUGCUUUAAAAUGUACCGUGUAAAUAUAAACACAUCCUAUCAGA